AGAGAAGCGGCUCCCGUCGGAGGCCGAGUCGUCGCCACGAUCGCCCCCUUGGUGGACUCGCAGGCCGAGCGGCUUCCCCGCAGAGCUCGAGGAGGGCAGACGGCGGCGGGGGCGCCAUGAGUCAGAGGCAGGUGCUGCAAGUGUUCGAGCAAUACCAGAAGGCCAGGACCCAGUUCGUGCAGAUGGUGGCGGAGCUGGCGACUAGACCCCAAAACAUCGAGACGCUGCAGAACGCGGAGUCUUGCUCUGUUGCCAGGCUAGAGUGCAGUGGCAUGAUCUCGGCUCACUACAACCUCCGCCUCCCAGGUUCAAGCGAUUCUCCUGCCUCAGCCUCCUGAGUAGCUGAGACUACAGAUGGAGUCUCAUUCACUCUGUCACCCAGGCUGGAGUGCAGUGGCACCAUCCUUGCCCACUGCAGCCUCCACCUCCCCGGAUCAAGUGAUUCUCCUGCCUCAGUCUCCCAAAGUGCUGGGAUUAAAGAGGCCUUGUUUAUCAGAUAUUGUGGCAACUAUUCAGACUGCUUUAAUUUGUGAACUCUAAAUUUCCAUGCAUUCACUCACCAUGGAUCUCUGGAUACCUAAUGGACAGGCAGGUGUAAUGUCUUUGCUGAGAACUCUUCUUCUGGACGUGGUCCCAACAAUUCAACAGACUGCUGCUUUGGCUCUUGGGAGACUGGCCAAUUAUAAUGAUGACCUAGCAGAAGCUGUUGUGAAGUGCGACAUUCUUCCACAGCUUGUUUAUUCAUUGGCAGAACAGAAUCGCUUCUACAAGAAAGCAGCUGCCUUUGUGUUACGAGCAGUUGGUAAACAUUCUCCCCAGCUAGCUCAGGCAAUAGUCGAUUGUGGAGCACUGGAUACGCUGGUCAUAUGCUUGGAAGAUUUUGACCCUGGAGUCAAGGAGGCUGCAGCCUGGGCACUUAGAUAUAUUGCAAGACAUAAUGCAGAACUGUCACAAGCUGUGGUGGAUGCAGGAGCUGUUCCUCUUUUAGUACUCUGUAUCCAGGAGCCAGAAAUUGCUUUGAAAAGGAUUGCUGCUUCGGCCCUCAGUGAUAUUGCAAAGCAUUCUCCAGAGUUAGCACAGACAGUAGUGGAUGCAGGAGCUGUUGCUCAUUUAGCCCAGAUGAUCCUGAACCCUGAUGCUAAAUUGAAGCAUCAGAUCCUUUCAGCUCUCAGUCAGGUUUCAAAACAUUCCGUGGAUCUGGCAGAAAUGGUUGUUGAAGCAGAGAUUUUUCCAGUUGUACUUACCUGUCUGAAGGACAAGGAUGAAUACGUGAAGAAAAAUGCUUCUACUUUAAUUAGAGAGAUUGCAAAACAUACACCCGAGCUUUCACAGCUGGUAGUUAACGCAGGAGGGGUUGCUGCCGUGAUUGACUGCAUUGGGUCCUGCAAAGGGAACACACGGCUGCCUGGCAUCAUGAUGCUUGGUUAUGUAGCAGCUCAUUCUGAGAACCUAGCAAUGGCAGUCAUCAUUUCUAAGGGUGUACCCCAGUUGUCAGUCUGCUUGUCAGAAGAACCGGAAGAUCAUAUUAAGGCUGCAGCUGCUUGGGCCUUAGGACAGAUUGGAAGACACACUCCUGAACACGCACGGGCUGUUGCAGUCACAAAUACUUUGCCAGUUCUGCUUUCUUUGUACAUGUCAACAGAAAGUUCUGAGGAUCUCCAAGUAAAAAGUAAAAAAGCCAUAAAGAAUAUCCUGCAAAAAUGUACCUACUUACCAGCCCUUGAACCAUUUCUAUAUGAUGCUCCUCCCAAUAUUCUGAAACAUGUGGUUGGACAGUUCAGUAAGGUGCUGCCGCAUGAUAGCAAAGCUCGACGACUUUUUGUAACAAGUGGUGGCCUUAAAAAAGUUCAAGAGAUAAAAGCAGAACCUGGUUCUCUCCUUCAAGAAUACAUCAACAGUAUUAACAGUUGUUACCCCGAGGAAAUAGUGAGGUAUUAUUCCCCUGGAUAUUCAGAUACACUUCUGCAGAGGGUGGACAGCUAUCAACCACUUAAUAACUGAGCAAAGUUAUAUUGUGAUACUCAAAUUCACAGCAGAGUAGUUUUGAGUAACAGUAAUUAAAUCCUUCUAAAUAUUUGAACUAAGUAUAUUCUAGAUUUAUUUAAUGGGAAAUACCUUUAGAUAAUAUUUUCUAAAUUUAUGUAAUACUUUAAACAUUCGUAGCUUGAAUAUGUGAGGAACUAUUCAUGGUCAUUCGCAUGCAUAGGAUUUGUUCUACAGGUAGAUUUUAAAAACACGUUAAAGGGCCUUAAGGCAUUUUGUUAUUCUGUUAAAAACCACACACACUCGUACAUGCAGACACCUCCAAUGAGAUAUAGUUAAGAGAUGGCAUUCAAAAACCCUAAAUUAUUCUAGCCAAUUUGUCAUAGGCAUAGGCAAGGAAAGCUGGCCUUGCUAACUAUAUAGUAGUAUACACAAGAGAAAUCUUUGAAGGAGGAAACUGAUGACAGAUAUACAGGGCACUUGAAGGAGACUCUGAUGCUAGUUAUAUAAGUGCAUUAACUUAAGACACGGACUCUGUGGGUAACCUGUUAGGUUUUACUAAGAAUUUAGGAAAAAUUUACUCCUCUUUAUCACAAGUUUUCCAAACCUCCUUCCCCACCCUAUCUAAAGUGUUCCUUACCUUUCAUGGGCCCAGCGAGGGUAGAAUUCAGAAUAGAGAGUUAUACUCCUGCAUACAUGCUCUCCCUCUCAUUGAAAGGUUUCUUAGUCUAGCUCUGCUCAUGAAUGAACAAAGAAGCAGGCAUGUAAAAUGGAUCCUUGUCCUAACGUCACUUUCCCAAGUUUCAAAAGUCACAUUUUCAGGUAUUUAAGGAAUAGUUUGAAGCUAAUACCAUCAGGCUCAGAGUUUACAUGCAUUUUUACUUAGGAAGUGGUAAACGGGUGAAAGAGGGUUUCAAUAAAAUUUUAAAUAAAAACAGCA